AGGAGCUUGCAGUAGCGGGCGGCAGAGCUGGAGUGAAGGGAGCUAGUGGUAAAGGGAGCUGGUGGAGGGGUGGCGGCAGGGGUAAGGGGCAGGGGACACCCUCUAGACGGAGAGCGGGCUCCGAGGUCCUGGCUGGCCCUCGGUGCGCCCGCCCCUGUGUUGGUCCCACAAUCCCUGGCAAUGAGAGGCCAGGGUUUAUUGGACAGAGUCAGUUGUGGGGUUCAGAGGGUCAGCAAUCAAUCAAUCCUCCGAAUCCAGAGAUUUAGACCCAGUCGUCCGUAUUAGGACUGGAGGGGGGUCAAUAGGUUCAGUGUUUGAGAUGCCAAGGGAACCUGUCUUUUGAUUUGGGGUUCAACAUACAGAGUUUAGGUAGCAGUCACCAUUAUGCUCAAAGCGGUGAUCCUGAUUGGAGGCCCUCAAAAGGGAACUCGCUUCAGACCUUUGUCUUUUGAGGUGCCCAAACCAUUGUUUCCUGUGGCAGGGGUCCCUAUGAUCCAACACCAUAUUGAAGCCUGUGCCCAGGUCCCUGGAAUGCAGGAGAUUCUGCUCAUUGGCUUCUACCAACCUGAUGAGCCCCUCACCCAGUUCCUAGAAGCCGCCCAGCAGGAGUUUAACCUUCCAGUCAGGUACCUGCAGGAAUUUGCCCCCCUAGGCACAGGGGGUGGUCUUUACCAUUUUCGAGACCAGAUCCUGGCUGGGAGCCCCGAGGCAUUCUUCGUGCUCAAUGCUGAUGUCUGCUCCGACUUCCCCUUGAGUGCUAUGUUGGAAGCCCACCGACGCCAGCGUCACCCUUUCUUACUCCUUGGCACUACGGCUAACAGGACGCAAUCCCUCAACUACGGCUGCAUCGUUGAGAAUCCACAGACACACGAGGUAUUGCACUAUGUGGAGAAACCCAGCACAUUUAUCAGUGACAUCAUCAACUGCGGCAUCUACCUCUUUUCUCCUGAAGCCUUGAAGCCUCUUCGGGAUGUCUUCCAGCGUAAUCAGCAGGAUGGGCAAUUCUGCCUUGCUCUGGGGGAGGACUCACCAGGCUUGUGGCCAGGGGCAGGUACCAUCCGCCUAGAGCAGGAUGUGUUUUCAGCCCUGGCAGGGCAGGGCCAGAUAUACGUGCAUCUCACUGAUGGUAUCUGGAGUCAGAUCAAGUCCGCAGGUUCAGCCCUCUACGCCUCCCGCCUCUACCUGAGCCGAUACCAGGACACUCACCCAGAACGGCUGGCCAAGCACACCCCAGGGGGCCCAUGGAUCCGAGGUACCCAGCCUGCCCCAAUUCCUAACCUUUGGCUUCCACCCCAGCCCUCUGAACCAGGAUUCUUGACCUCGAGUCCAGAGUUAAAGCCUCAAUCCCUGCCCCUUCCUGAUCAAAUUCGGUUUGGGAUAUUUGCCCCCAGGGCCUCUCUUCUGCUUCUAGGGAAUGUGUACAUCCACCCGACCGCCAAGGUGGCCCCCUCGGCUGUGCUGGGCCCCAACGUCUCCAUCGGGAAGGGGGUGACCGUGGGUGAGGGUGUGCGGCUCCGGGAGAGCAUCGUCCUCCAUGGAGCCACUUUGCAGGAGCACACGUGUGUUCUGCAUAGCAUCGUGGGCUGGGGGAGCACCGUGGGACGCUGGGCCCGCGUGGAGGGUACCCCCAGUGACCCUAACCCCAACGAUCCCCGAGCCCGCAUGGACAGUGAGAGCCUCUUCAAGGACGGGAAGCUGCUGCCUGCUAUCACCAUCCUGGGCUGCCGAGUCCGGAUCCCUGCCGAGGUGCUCAUCCUGAACUCGAUUGUUCUGCCACACAAGGAGCUGAGCCGAAGCUUCACCAACCAGAUCAUCCUCUGAGUAGGGCUGCCAGAAGGCCCCCAGCUCCUACCCACUCCCCUUGAGGCUGCUGCCUGCUUGGCCAGCCUCUGUCCAGAAAGGACCAGAGAAAGCCAGGCUGGAUCGUCACAUGCCGGGGAGCAAUGUGGAUGGCCUGGGGACUCCUGGGUUUUCUCCCUCCCGACUCCCUAAUAAACCCCGUGAACCUUGGA